AGCAUAUGCAACCUUGGGCUGGAAAUGACAUGGUGGUUUCAUUUGGAGUCCUUAGUCUGGCUCAAGUAUAGAUGAUGCUUCAACUUUUCCUGAUGCCUUGUCUUGAGACAGAGAUUCCAUCUCCACCAUCAACCUGCUAGAGAGGAAUUUACACUUCUCCAUGGAGACCUUCCUUUCAGAAAACUCAGUAGGCAUGGUGAAUAUAGUUCAUGAUGAUAUAUUGAAUUAUUGGAAAAUGCCAAGAAAAUGGAUGUUAAGUGUUCUCGCCACAAGAAUGAUGACUAUAUGAGUCACAUUGAAAAGAUGCAACCAAGCCUGGGCACAAUGGCUUAUGCCUAUAAUCUCAGCACUUUUGUAGGCUGAAGUGGGAGGAUCGCAUGAGUCCAGGAGGUUCAGACCAGCGUUGGCAACAGAGUGAGAGACCCUGUCUAUGUUAAUAAAUAAAUAAAUAAAUAAAUAAAUAAAUAAAUAAAUAGAAAAAAAAAGAUGGAACCAGAGAAUGACACAGGGAUUUCAGAAUUUGUUCUUCUGGGACUUUCUGAGGAACCAGAAUUGCAGCCCUUCCUCUUUGGGCUGUUUCUGUCCAUGUACCUGGUCACUGUGCUCGGGAAUCUGCUCAUCAUCCUGGCCACAAUCUCAGACUCCCACCUCCACACCCCCAUGUACUUCUUCCUCUCCAACCUGUCCUUUGCAGACAUCUGUUUCAUCUCCACUACAAUCCCAAAGAUGCUCAUUAACAUCCAGACACAGAGCAGAGUCAUCACCUAUGCAGGCUGCAUCACCCAGAUGUGCUUUUUUGUACUUUUUGGAGGGUUAGACAGCUUACUCCUGGCUGUGAUGGCCUAUGAUCGGUUUGUGGCCAUCUGUCAUCCUCUGCACUACACAGUCAUCAUGAACCCUCGGCUCUGUGGACUCCUGGUUCUGGCAUCCUGGAUGAUUGCUGCCCUGAAUUCCUUGUCACAAAGCUUAAUGGUAUUGUGGCUGUCCUUCUGCACAGACUUGGAAAUCCCCCACUUUUUCUGUGAACUUAAUCAGGUCAUCCACCUUGCCUGUUCUGACACCUUUCUUAAUGACAUGGGGAUGUAUUUUGCAGCAGGGCUGCUGGCUGGUGGUCCCCUUGUGGGGAUCCUUUGCUCUUACUCUAAGAUAGUUUCCUCCAUACGUGCAAUCUCAUCAGCUCAGGGGAAGUACAAGGCAUUUUCCACCUGUGCAUCACACCUCUCAGUUGUCUCUUUAUUUUGUUGUACGGGCCUAGGUGUGUACCUUACUUCUGCUGCAACCCACAACUCACACACAAGUGCAACAGCCUCAGUGAUGUACACUGUGGCCACCCCCAUGCUGAACCCCUUUAUCUACAGUCUGAGGAAUAAAGACAUAAAGAGGGCUCUGAAAAUGUCCUUCAGAGGAAAGCAAUAAAAGGGCCAUUUUUCAAGAAAUAACUGUGAUUUCAGAGCUUUAAGUCUCAUACUCAGAAAUUGUGAUUCACGAAUCAGGUUGUGAAAGUGGAAUUUGCUCCUUCUAUUUUUUCUCAGAGUUUCAAUUUCUUUGAUCUCAACUGACAUAGAAUUUAAUGUAUUCCUUUAUAAAGCUUUCCGCUCUCUGAUAUCCAAUCUUUUUUUUUUUUUUUUUUUUGUCAUUUUCCUACUUUCCCAAUGUUUUUCCCAAACUAGGGUCAGAAACAAGGUGGAGAUUCCUAUUUUUCUCCUACACUUGUGGGUUGCAUUAGUCCUGCAGAAUCAAUUGCACCUGGCAGCCAUAAGGUCAUUAAUAUAAUUUUAUUUUAGAUAAAUAUCUGAGAAGACAGUUUUUCACUUUGAGCUUAUUCCUUUCUCCACCACCACCUUAAGUGUUCUUCCUGGUCAUGUAAACUUUACCCCACACGAGUGUGCAUUUUAGCUCAUCAUGGCAUUUAUUUUUUUAGAUGGAGUCUCGCUCUGUCACCCAGGCUGAAGUGCAGUGGCAUCAUCUCAGCUCACUGCAACCUCUGCCUCCUGGGUUCAAGCAAUUCUCCUGCCUCAGCCUCCCAAGGAGCUGGGAUUACAGGCAUGUACCACCAUGCCCGGCUAAUUUUUGUAUUUUUAGUAGGGAAGGGGUUUCACCAUGUUGGCCAGGCUGGUCUCGAACUCCUACCCUCAGGGGAUCCGCCUGCCUCGGCCCCCCAAAGUGCUGUCAUCAUGGCAUUUUAUCCUACUCAUUAGGGUCCUGUCCUCUAUUCAGUUCAGUGUCCACCGUGCCUGCUCAAUUCCCUGGAAAGAGUAAGAAGGUAAAAAUUUCCUAUCAAGUGCAGGCACGGUGGCUCAGGCCUGUAAUCCCAGCACUUUGGGAGGCCAAGGCGGGCGGAUCACCUGAGGUAGGGAGUUGGAGACCAGGCUGACCAACAGGGAGAAACCCCGUCUCUACCAAAAAUACAAAAUUAGCUGGGCGUGGUGGCGCAUGCCUGUAAUCCCAGCUACGCAGGAGACUGAGGCAGGAGAAUGGUUUGAACCCGGGAGACGGAGGUUGCAGUGAGCCGAGAUCACAGCAUUGCCCUCCAGUCUGGGCAACAAGAGCGAAACUCCAUCUCAAAAAAAAAAAAAUUGCCUAUCAAAUUCACACUUCAAGUGUAGUCUGCACAGAAAAAUAAAUUUGUGUGAAUCAAUUGAUUUCAUCUGGACUUAGAUUACAAAAACACCUGAAAGAAUAUGGAUUAAAAAAUUUAUUCAUAACUGAAAGAAUAAAUGCUUAAUGGGGUGGGUACCCCAUUCACCAUGAUGUGAUUAUUAUAUAACGCAUGCCUGUAUCAAAACAUCUCAUGUACCCCAUAAGUAUAUACAUCUACUAUGUACCCACAAAAAUAUAAAAGAAAAAAAGAUGGAGUAAAAUUUUUGGCCCGGCAUGGUGGCUCACGCCUGUAAUCCCAGAACUUUGGGAGGCUGAGGCAAGUGGAUUACCUGAAGUCAGGAGUUCAAGACCAGGCUGGCCAACAUGGUGAAACCCUGUCUCUACUAAAAAUGCAAAAAUUAGCCGGGCAUGGUGGCACAUGCCUGUAAUCCCAGCUACUCAGGAGGCUGAGGCAGGAGAAUCACUUGAACCUGGGAGGUGGAGGUUGCAGUGAGCUGAGAUCACACCACUGCACUCCAGCCUGGGUGACAGAGACUCCAUCUCAAAAAAAAAAAUCAGUCAUACAUUGAAUUGCAUUGGGAGAUUUGAUCUGAUGAUAUACAUCUACUUAUAGAGGCUUGGUGCCCAUUUGUAAUGAGGUUUGUUAGUCCAAGGGAAGGAUUUGGAAUCACAGUCUAUGUAAUUUCAUUAUAUCAUUUUACUGUUUCUGCUUAAAAAUUUACAGUGCUACACACAAAUAAGACUCCUUCUGUUGUCCUGCUUAAAAUCUUCCUUUUAAAAUAUUGUGUCUUAGCCAUUAAAAUGUAGGUAAGUGAACAAUGUGUGUAUUUAACUUAUCAUCAGUUCAUUUGUCUCUUUUAUACUCUAACUCUCUUCAACCCUUAUAAUCAAAUGAUGACUCACAAAGGAACCUGAAUUUCUAACCAGCAUUGGCUUGGAGAAUAGAGACUUGUGAAUCAGAAUCACAAUUUAUAUCUACAAAUACAUACACGUUCUUUCAAAAUAUUCUAGCUCCCUAGAAGGGAAUCUAAUAGGUAG